AGUAUGUUUUGCAGACAAGACCCAGAGAAGUCCAGACUGGACUUGUUGCAGACUGCAAAACUGCCAUUGGAAGGCCUCCGUCCCAGUCCUUCUACAGAGUAGCCAGUGGGAUUCCCAGCCAUGGGCGAGGUGACAGCAGAGGAGGUGGAGAAGUUCCUGGACUCGAAUAUUGGCUUUGCCAAACAGUACUACAACCUCCACUACCGGGCCAAGCUCAUCUCCGACCUCCUUGGGGCCAAGGAGGCUGCCGUGGACUUCAGCAACUACCACUCCCCGAGCAGCAUGGAGGAGAGCGAAAUCAUCUUUGAUCUCCUGCGGGACUUUCAGGAGAAUUUACAGACAGAGAAAUGCAUCUUCAAUGUCAUGAAGAAGCUGUGCUUCCUCCUGCAGGCAGACCGCAUGAGCCUGUUCAUGUACCGGACCCGCAAUGGCAUCGCAGAGCUGGCCACCAGGCUUUUCAAUGUCCACAAGGAUGCUGUCCUCGAGGACUGCCUGGUGAUGCCCGACCAAGAGAUCGUCUUCCCUUUGGACAUGGGCAUCGUGGGCCAUGUCGCACACUCUAAGAAGAUUGCUAACGUCCCCAACACAGAGGAGGAUGAGCAUUUCUGUGACUUUGUGGACAUCCUCACAGAGUACAAGACCAAGAACAUCUUGGCUUCCCCCAUAAUGAAUGGGAAGGAUGUGGUGGCCAUAAUCAUGGCUGUGAAUAAAGUGGAUGGAUCCCACUUCACCAAGAGAGAUGAAGAGAUUCUUCUCAAGUACCUCAAUUUUGCAAAUCUAAUCAUGAAGGUGUACCACCUGAGUUACCUGCACAACUGUGAAACUCGACGUGGCCAGAUACUGCUGUGGUCUGGGAGCAAAGUCUUUGAAGAACUUACGGACAUCGAACGACAGUUCCACAAAGCCCUGUACACAGUCCGUGCUUUCCUCAACUGUGACAGAUACUCUGUGGGUCUCUUAGACAUGACCAAGCAGAAGGAAUUUUUUGAUGUGUGGCCGGUUCUGAUGGGUGAAGUUCCACCUUACUCUGGUCCCAGGACUCCGGAUGGAAGAGAAAUUAACUUUUACAAGGUCAUUGACUACAUCCUGCAUGGCAAAGAGGACAUCAAAGUCAUCCCGAAUCCACCUCCUGACCAUUGGGCUUUAGUAAGCGGUCUCCCAGCUUAUGUUGCCCAGAAUGGCCUGAUUUGCAACAUCAUGAAUGCGCCUGCGGAGGACUUUUUUGCAUUUCAGAAAGAACCUCUGGAUGAGUCUGGAUGGAUGAUUAAAAAUGUGCUUUCAAUGCCGAUUGUGAACAAGAAGGAAGAAAUUGUUGGAGUGGCCACAUUUUACAAUCGUAAAGAUGGGAAGCCCUUUGAUGAAAUGGAUGAGACGCUCAUGGAGUCUUUGACUCAAUUUCUGGGCUGGUCUGUCUUAAAUCCUGACACCUAUGAGUCAAUGAAUAAACUUGAAAAUAGGAAGGAUAUUUUCCAGGACAUAGUAAAAUAUCAUGUGAAGUGUGACAAUGAAGAAAUUCAGAAAAUCUUGAAAACCAGAGAGGUGUAUGGGAAGGAGCCAUGGGAGUGUGAGGAAGAGGAGCUGGCUGAGAUCCUGCAAGCGGAGCUGCCAGAUGCAGAUAAAUACGAAAUUAAUAAAUUUCACUUCAGUGACUUACCCCUAACAGAACUGGAGCUGGUAAAAUGUGGAAUACAGAUGUAUUAUGAGCUCAAAGUGGUGGAUAAAUUUCACAUUCCACAAGAGGCCCUGGUGCGGUUCAUGUACUCCCUGAGUAAGGGCUACCGCAAGAUCACCUACCACAACUGGCGGCACGGCUUCAACGUGGGGCAGACCAUGUUCUCCCUGCUGGUGACGGGAAAGCUGAAGCGCUACUUCACGGACCUAGAGGCCUUGGCCAUGGUCACUGCUGCUUUCUGCCAUGACAUUGACCACAGAGGCACCAAUAACCUCUACCAGAUGAAAUCCCAGAACCCACUGGCCAAGCUCCAUGGGUCCUCUAUCUUGGAAAGACACCACUUGGAGUUUGGCAAAACACUGCUCAGAGACGAGAGCCUGAAUAUCUUUCAAAACCUCAAUCGUCGACAGCAUGAGCAUGCCAUCCACAUGAUGGACAUUGCAAUCAUUGCCACAGACCUCGCCCUGUAUUUCAAGAAGAGGACGAUGUUCCAAAAGAUCGUGGAUCAGUCUAAGACAUAUGAGAGUGAACAGGAGUGGACACAGUACAUGAUGCUGGAGCAGACACGGAAGGAAAUCGUUAUGGCCAUGAUGAUGACCGCCUGUGAUCUCUCAGCCAUCACCAAACCCUGGGAGGUGCAGAGCCAGGUAGCUCUGCUGGUGGCUGCUGAAUUCUGGGAACAAGGUGACCUGGAGCGCACGGUGCUGCAACAGAAUCCCAUUCCCAUGAUGGACAGAAACAAAGCAGAUGAACUCCCUAAGCUUCAAGUCGGCUUCAUUGACUUUGUUUGCACCUUCGUCUACAAGGAAUUCUCCCGUUUCCACGAGGAGAUCACCCCAAUGUUGGACGGGAUCACCAACAAUCGCAAGGAGUGGAAGGCGCUUGCUGAUGAGUACGAUGCCAAGAUGAAGGUGCAGGAGGAGAAGAAGCAGAAACAGCAGUCGGCCAAGUCAGCAGCCGCAGGAAAUCAGCCGGGGGGAAACCCCAGCCCAGGGGGUGCAACUACAUCCAAGUCCUGCUGCAUCCAGUAACACCACUGGGGAUGUGCUGGCUGGACGGCACCACCCUUUCCUGGGAAGAGAUGACUCAAGCCAGUGGAAGACCACACACCUUGAGAAGUAGAAGAGUCAUAGGAUUUGAAAGCUGUUAGAGAAUUUAGCUUCCAGGACUGUUCAAUCUUUUGGCUUCCCUGGGCCACAUUGGAAGAAUUGUCUUGGGUCACACAUAAAAUACAGUAACACUAAUGAUAGCUGUUGAACUUAAAAAAAAAAAUCGCCAAAAAAAAAAAUUUCAUAAUGUUUUAAGAAAGUUUAUGAAUUUGUGUUGGGCCGCAUUCAAAGCCGUCCUGGGCUGCAUGUGGCCCACGGGCCGUGGGUUGAACAAGCUUGGCUUAUACCUUAUCCAGUGGCUUUUAAACAUUCUUUUAGUCUUGAGAACUGCCUAUUGAGCUAAAACCAAUAUUCUAGCUUUCAUAGACAUCAGUUAAACAUUUAAUUACAUUUAAUUAAUGCCAGAUUCACUGGCUUGCUUAGAAUCAUUUUUGUUCUUAUACUUUCAGUUAAUGUAUUGUAAAAAUUUUCAAUCAUUUUCAAAAGUAGAGAAUUGUACGUUGAAUCCCCACAUACCCAUCACCCAGAUUCCAAUAUCAAGAUUUUGCUACAUGCAUUUCGUCUGUCCUUUUUACAUUUUCUUUUCAAUUUUUUUUCUUACCUGAAGUGUUUAAAGGCAAAUCCUGGCCAGGCGUGGUGGCUCACACCUGUAAUCCCAGCACUUCAGGAGGCUGAGGUGGGCAGACUGCAUGAGCCCAGGAGUCUGAGACCAACCUGAGCAAAAUGGCAAAACCCUGUCUCUACAAAAAAUACAAAAAUUAGCACUCACCUGUAGUCUCAGCUACCUGGGAGGCAGAGGUGAGAGGAUCUCUUGAACCCAGGAGGCGGAAGUUGCAGUGAGCUGAGAUCAUGCUACUGCACUCCAGCUUGGGCGACCGAGCGAGACUCUGACUCAAACAAAAGCAAAAGAAAAGGCAAAUCCCAAACAUAUCAUUUCACACCUCUACUAUCUCAUCUUUAAAGAAAUAAGUAUGUUUUCUAACAUAACCACAUCACUGGCCCAUGCAACCAAUGCCUGCCUAAUACCCAGCUGUGAUCUAUGCUUUGAUGGGCUGCACAGACCCCAAGCUUCAGCAAAGGACUUGGGACCCCACCAGCUUUGAGUGCUGUUGACAGACCCUUAGUAUCAACCCCAUCAGGUGUUACUGCAGCCUUCCCCAGGGUGGCCUACACCCAAUGACUGAUCCAUGCCAGGUGGAGAGGCCUGGCCAUCUUGGCUGAGCAUGGGAUAACUGUGCAGGGCUGUUCCAGCUCCACGACUCCUCGUGGGGUCCACUAAGGCUGUCGCUGGGCUCACAUCCCAACUCGACUUCUCCCUCUGCCCACUCCUAUUUCCUUCCCUUCCCCAAGCAUCGGUCCCCAGGGCACUGCUUAAUAAGCAUCCUGCAGACUAAGUCCAUUUUAGAGUCUGCUUUCUGGGACACCCAACUUGUGAUGCCAGCCCUUAAUCAACCUUCCUUCAUUCUCAUGAACGUUUUCAAUGGUUGGCUUGCCUGAAUCUGAUCCAAACAAAUUCACAUAUUGAAUUUAGUUGUUUCUUUUUGUUGGUUUUUAGAAAAAAGAAGAUGUACUUUUUAUUCUUGGAUUUUUCAUUGAUUUCACAGAGUAUAAAUUAAGUCAGAUUAUUCUCAAUUCCAGAACUUCUGUUUCUUAAAUUAGCAGGCAUUCUGUUGGUUUAAAAAGAUAGAUGUUGGCCGGGCGCGGUGGCUCACGCCUGUAAUUCCAGCACUUUGGGAGGCCAAGGUGGGUGGAUCACCUGAGGUCAGGAGUUCAAGACCAGCCUGGCCAACAUGGUGAAACCCCAUCUCUACUAAAAAUACAAAAAUUAGCUGGGUGUGGUGGUGUGCACCUGUAAUCCCAGCUACUCAGGAGGCUGAGGCAGGAGAAUCGCUUGAACCUGGGAGGCGAAGGUUGCAGUGAGCUGAGAUCAUGCCACUGCACUCCAGCCUGGGCAACAAGAGCAAGACUCCGUCUCAAAAAAAAAAAAAAGAAAAAAAAAAGAUGUGGCAGAUAGAAUUUCUCUCUUUCUCUAUCUUUCAUGACGAGGUCUCACUCUGUCGCCCAGGCUGGAGUGCAGUGGUAUGACCAUAGCUCACUGGAGCCCCAGCUGCCCGGGCUCAAGCAAUCCUCCAUCUCAGCUUACCAAGCAGCGGUGACCACAGGCAUGCACCACCAUGCCCAGCUAAUUUUUUAAAACCUAUCUUUGUAGACAUGGGGUCUCAUUCUGUUGCCCAGGCUGGCCUCAAACUCCUGACUUCAAGCAAUCCUCCUGCCUCAGCCUCCCAAAGUGUUGGGAUUACAGGCGUGAGCCACUGCACCUGGCCAGGACUUAUUUCUUUUAAACCGAAUCUAAGUAUGUUCUGGCAAGUAUGCAAUACCUAGCGGAAUGCACUGGCCUGAUCAGCAUUCAUACCAUAGUAACUGAUGUUGAAAACAGCACAAAUAAACCAGAAGUUGAAAAUGGCAAUAACAUGCUAAAAAUUUGCAAGUCAAUUUGUUACACUUGUCCAAAUCUUGAUUUUUUUUCCUUCUCUAUCGUUCCCCCCCCACCACCAGCUUUAUGGAGGUAUAAUUAGCAAAUAAAAAGUAUACAUAUUUAAGGUAUACACUGUGAUGUUUUGAUAUACAUUGUGAAAUGGUUACCAUAAUUAAGCUAAUUAAUAUAUCCAUCACCUCACAUAGCCAUGGUUAAGUUUCUGAAGUCUCUUUUAAUCUACAAAGUACUCCUUCCUUUUUUCCAUUGUCAUCACCUUGCAGAAACAGAGUCAGUUUUCCCACAUUCUGUAUUUAUCUGUUUGUUUCUUUGUGGCCGCAUGUAACACAUUCCUCUGUCUCAUUCUAAUAAAUGGACAUUAGCUCUAGAA